AGUGGGCCGUUGCCUUACAGUUGCUGAGAGGAGGCGAGAGGCGGGGGCGCUAGGGCCGAGAUCAUGUCUGACUGGGAGAGGUUUCCUUGGCAGCAGAGGACGCUAGGUUUGGGAUGAAAGAAGCUGGGCAGAUGCAAAAUCUGGAGAGCGCGAGGGCCGGGCGGUCAGUCAGCACCCAGACUGGCAGCAUGACCGGUCAGAUACCAAGGCUUUCUAAAGUCAACCUUUUCACUCUGCUCAGCCUCUGGAUGGAGCUCUUUCCAGCAGAAGCCCAGCGGCAAAAAUCUCAGAAAAAUGAAGAGGGAAAGCAUGGACCCUUAGGAGAUAAUGAAGAGAGGACCAGAGUAUCUACUGACAAAAGACAGGUAAAGAGAACUGGUCUUGUGGUGGUGAAAAACAUGAAAAUUGUUGGUCUCCACUGUUCUAGUGAAGAUUUACAUGCCGGGCAGAUUGCUCUUAUUAAACAUGGGUCAAGGCUGAAAAACUGUGAUCUUUAUUUUUCCAGAAAACCAUGUUCUGCUUGUUUGAAAAUGAUUGUAAAUGCUGGAGUUAACCGAAUUUCAUACUGGCCUGCUGAUCCAGAAAUAAGUUUGCUUACGGAGGCUUCUAGUUCUGAAGAUGCAAAGUUAGAUGCCAAAGCAGUGGAAAGAUUGAAGUCAAACAGUCGGGCCCAUGUGUGUGUCUUACUUCAACCUUUGGUGUGUUAUAUGGUGCAGUUUGUAGAGGAGACCUCUUACAAAUGUGACUUUAUUCAAAAAAUUACAAAAACAUUGCCGGAUGCUAACACUGACUUUUAUUAUGAAUGUAAACAAGAAAGAAUAAAAGAAUAUGAAAUGUUAUUUUUGGUUUCAAAUGAAGAAAUGCAUAAGCAAAUACUGAUGACUAUAGGUUUGGAGAACCUGUGUGAAAAUCCAUACUUUAGCAAUCUAAGGCAAAACAUGAAAGACCUUAUCCUACUUUUGGCCACAGUAGCUUCCAGUGUGCCGAACUUUAAACACUUCGGAUUUUACCGUAGCAAUCCAGAACAGAUUAAUGAAAUUCACAAUCAAAGUUUGCCACAGGAAAUUGCAAGGCACUGCAUGGUUCAGGCCAGGUUAUUGGCAUAUCGAACUGAGGAUCAUAAAACAGGAGUUGGGGCAGUCAUUUGGGCAGAAGGGAAAUCUAGAAGUUGUGAUGGAACAGGUGCCAUGUACUUUGUAGGAUGUGGUUACAAUGCUUUUCCUGUUGGAUCUGAGUAUGCUGACUUCCCACACAUGGAUGACAAGCAGAAAGACAGAGAAAUAAGGAAAUUCAGAUACAUCAUACAUGCGGAACAGAAUGCCUUGACAUUUAGGUGUCAAGAAAUAAAACCAGAAGAAAGAAGCAUGAUUUUUGUGACAAAGUGCCCAUGUGAUGAGUGUGUACCUUUAAUUAAAGGUGCAGGCAUAAAACAAAUCUAUGCAGGAGAUGUAGAUGUUGGAAAAAAGAAGGCAGACAUCUCUUACAUGAGGUUCGGGGAGCUUGAAGGUGUUAGCAAAUUUACGUGGCAGCUGAAUCCAUCAGGAGCUUAUGGUCUUGAACAAAAUGAGCCUGAAAGGAGAGAAAAUGGUGUGUUGAGACCUGUCCCACAGAAGGAAGAGCAGCACCAGGACAAGAAGCUGCGCCUCGGAAUCCACUAAGAAGGCCUGUCUACACUGCAGGGGAACCUCAAGAACUUUUCAUUGCACUUCUAAAAUUCAGCCUUGUUCAUUCAGAAAAUAAGGAUGGAUUUUGUGAAUAAUUGAAAAGAUUUUUUAAGGAAGCUAAUUUAUUUCUAGGAUACAAAUGGUGUUAAUAAGAAUAUUUGUCUUUUAGAUUUAUGUGUGGGUUUUCCAUAAUGUAGUAGUGUGUUAUUUUAUUACACGAAAUGAGGGAGCAAUAACUUCAACCAAUGUAAUCACCAACAGGGACUGAUUUCUAUUUAUCUUGACUUUAUAUUAGCCAAUUUGAAAGGGUCUGCUUCACAAGAGGUCAUGCCUCUGCAGGGAAUCACACACCUUUUGAGAAAUAUUAAUUCUUUUGAAUUACAAGAGUGACAGUUAGUAAACUGCUCCAGGGAAAUAAGUGUCAUCUUUUAAGAGUCAGUGUAUAGCAAACCAAAAGAUCACAUUUAUACCCAAAGCUUUCUAGUAAUCAGAAUUUACUUAAUUAGAAUUGACUCAUAAAAAUAAAGUUAGUGGACUUUGUCUCCAUUUUUAAAGUAUAUUUUGUAAAUGUUAAUUCUGUGGUCCUGUUUAUCACAGACUUUGGGUAGCAAUAGGAAGAGAGUGUUAUUCUGAGACAGUGUCGCUGCUUGAUAUCACUGACUCUUGAAAUCACUAACAGUGAACCUCAAAUUUGGUUAUGAUGUUAACAGAGAAGAAAUAUUUGAGUCUGGAAUAUUGAAACUAGCUUUCCUAGAAUUCCAUUAAUAAAUGCUGCUCCCCCAUAUAGUCUUCCCUUCUGUAUAAUUAACAUAGGUUGUCUCAUGGCUUUGAUCUUCAAAAGGAAGAGCCUUUUAAAAACAUUUGCCAACCUCAAGAAUAAAUACUGAAAGUCUUGAAAGUAUGGUCAUUUCAGCUAUUCCAGAUUGCUGUCUGUGAUUUCUCACAUUUUUAUUUGCUGAGAAACAUUCAGAAAAUUAUUCCAAAAAUGAAGGUACAUUUUCUGUUCUCUCCUAGGUUAGAGAGGGGUGGCCUGGGGUGCUUCAUGAGAAAUGUCUUCCUGGAUCUGCGGUGGUCAGGUUUGCCUCUGCUUUUGUUCCCUGCCUUUCCGCCACAUCACACGGCCUCACUGGGCUUCCUACCAGUUUCUCAGAAUUACACGCACGACCAUCCAAACAUUGGCUCCAUGCCAGGGCUGUGACUGCAGCCUGUGUAGGACCAUGGGGAGUUCAGAGUCAUCAUACAAGGCAGCCAAGAACUGCCAUAAACACUACACAGAUGGAGGGCAUGGGAUAGGACAGGAGAGGAGGUGAUGUACACUUAGAGGUAACUAAGGCUAGUUUGAAAACCGUGAAUUAAGAUAUUCUUAUCAGUAUAAAAACACUGAGAUUGCUUACCUCCCAAAUUGCUUUAUUGUAUUAACUCUCAUGCUUCAGCUCUUGGAUUUGUUGUUUCUAACUAACAUGUCAUGUACACCAAACAUUUUAUAAAUCAAUCAGUAAAUAUUUUGUAAGACCCAAAAUCCUGGCAUAUUGCCAGGUCUGUGGAUUUGCCUGUUGGGUGUUGGGAUGGGAUAUCAGAGGAAGAAGCAUACAAGUGGGAAAAACUGUGAUUAGAAAGGGAAAAAUAGGCAUUUCCACAGUACUAUUAAGAGAGGCAUGAUAAUGCCAUUUUUUUUCUUCUGUACAACUGGUCAGAUUUCAAUAAAUAAUCAUUGAUGGUUUA